CCCUUCCCCCCGCCUCUGGCCUCGGGGAAGGAGCAGGAGGCAGCCCAGGCGGAGCGGGAGGAGCUGGCAGCGGGGCGCAUGCCAGGCGGGGGUCCUCAGGGCGCCCCAGCCGCCGCCGGCGGCGGCGGCGUGAGCCACCGCGCAGGCAGCCGGGAUUGCUUACCACCUGCAGCGUGCUUUCGGAGGCGGCGGCUGGCACGGAGGCCGGGCUACAUGAGAAGCUCGACAGGGCCUGGGAUCGGGUUCCUUUCCCCAGCAGUGGGCACACUGUUCCGGUUCCCAGGAGGGGUGUCUGGCGAGGAGUCCCACCACUCGGAGUCCAGGGCCAGACAGUGUGGCCUUGACUCGAGAGGCCUCUUGGUCCGGAGCCCUGUUUCCAAGAGUGCAGCAGCCCCUACUGUGACCUCUGUGAGAGGAACCUCGGCGCACUUUGGGAUUCAGCUCAGAGGUGGCACCAGAUUGCCUGACAGGCUUAGCUGGCCGUGUGGCCCUGGGAGUGCUGGGUGGCAGCAAGAGUUUGCAGCCAUGGAUAGUUCUGAGACCCUGGACGCCAGCUGGGAGGCAGCCUGCAGCGAUGGAGCAAGGCGUGUCCGGGCAGCAGGCUCUCUGCCAUCAGCAGAGUUGAGUAGCAACAGCUGCAGCCCUGGCUGUGGCCCUGAGGUCCCCCCAACCCCUCCUGGCUCUCACAGUGCCUUUACCUCAAGCUUUAGCUUUAUUCGGCUCUCGCUUGGCUCUGCCGGGGAACGUGGAGAAGCAGAAGGCUGCCCACCAUCCAGAGAGGCUGAGUCCCAUUGCCAGAGCCCCCAGGAGAUGGGAGCCAAAGCUGCCAGCUUGGACGGGCCUCACGAGGACCCGCGAUGUCUCUCUCGGCCCUUCAGUCUCUUGGCUACACGGGUCUCUGCAGACUUGGCCCAGGCCGCAAGGAACAGCUCCAGGCCAGAGCGUGACAUGCAUUCUUUACCAGACAUGGACCCUGGCUCCUCCAGUUCUCUGGAUCCCUCACUGGCUGGCUGUGGUGGUGAUGGGAGCAGCGGCUCAGGGGAUGCCCACUCUUGGGACACCCUGCUCAGGAAAUGGGAGCCAGUGCUGCGGGACUGCCUGCUGAGAAACCGGAGGCAGAUGGAGGUAAUAUCCUUAAGAUUAAAACUUCAGAAACUUCAGGAAGAUGCAGUUGAGAAUGAUGAUUAUGAUAAAGUAGAGACGGGGUUUCACUAUGUUGGUCAAGCUGGUCUUGAACUCCUGACCUCAAGCAAUCCACCUGCUUCGGCCUCCCAAAGUGCUGGGAUUACAGCUGAGACGUUACAACAAAGAUUAGAAGACCUGGAACAAGAGAAAAUCAGCCUGCACUUUCAACUUCCUUCAAGGCAGCCAGCUCUUAGCAGUUUCCUGGGUCACCUGGCAGCACAAGUCCAGGCUGCCUUGCGCCGUGGGGCCACUCAGCAGGCCAGCGGAGAUGACACCCACACCCCACUGAGAAUGGAGCCGAGGCUGUUGGAACCCACUGCUCAGGACAGCUUGCACGUGUCCAUCACGAGACGAGACUGGCUUCUUCAGGAAAAGCAGCAGCUACAGAAAGAAAUCGAAGCUCUCCAAGCAAGGAUGUUUGUGCUGGAAGCCAAAGAUCAACAGCUGAGAAGGGAAAUAGAGGAGCAAGAGCAGCAACUCCAGUGGCAGGGCUGCGACCUGACCCCACUGGUGGGCCAGCUGUCCCUGGGUCAGCUGCAGGAGGUCAGCAAGGCCUUGCAGGACACCCUGGCCUCAGCCGGUCAGAUUCCCUUCCAUGCAGAGCCACCGGAAACCAUAAGGAGCCUCCAGGAAAGAAUAAAAUCCCUCAACUUGUCACUUAAAGAAAUCACUACUAAGGUGUGUAUGAGUGAGAAAUUCUGCAGCACCCUGAGGAAGAAAGUUAACGAUAUUGAAACCCAACUACCAGCCUUGCUUGAAGCCAAAAUGCAUGCCAUAUCAGGAAACCAUUUCUGGACGGCUAAAGACCUCACCGAGGAGAUUAGAUCAUUAACAUCAGAGAGAGAAGGGCUGGAGGGACUCCUCAGCAAGCUGUUGGUGUUGAGUUCCAGGAAUGUCAAAAAGCUGGGAAGUGUUAAAGAAGAUUACAACAGACUGAGAAGAGAAGUGGAGCACCAGGAGACUGCCUAUGAAACAAGUGUGAAGGAAAAUACUAUGAAGUACAUGGAAACACUUAAGAAUAAACUGUGCAGCUGCAAGUGUCCACUGCUUGGGAAAGUGUGGGAAGCUGACUUGGAAGCUUGUCGAUUGCUUAUCCAGAGCCUACAGCUCCAGGAAGCCAGGGGAAGCCUGUCUGUAGAAGAUGAGAGGCAGAUGGAUGACUUAGAGGGAGCUGCUCCUCCUAUUCCCCCCAGGCUCCACUCCGAGGAUAAAAGGAAGACCCCUUUGAAGGUAUUGGAAGAAUGGAAGACUCACCUCAUCCCCUCUCUGCACUGUGCUGGAGGUGAACAGAAAGAGGAAUCUUACAUCCUUUCUGCAGAACUUGGAGAAAAGUGUGAAGACAUAGGCAAGAAGCUAUUGUACUUGGAAGAUCAACUUCACACAGCAAUCCACAGUCAUGAUGAAGAUCUCAUUCAGUCUCUCAGGAGGGAGCUCCAGAUGGUGAAGGAAACUCUGCAGGCCAUGAUCCUGCAGCUCCAGCCAGCAAAGGAGGCGGGAGAAAGAGAAGCUGCAGCUUCCUGCAUGACAGCUGGUGUCCACGAAGCACAAGCCUGAGGAGUGACGGGAUGGGGGAGGGAGGUGGGCCACCAUGUUUGGACCCGGGGGGCUGCUCUUCCCUCCCCCGCCAUAGCUAAGAUGCCUGAAUCAAUUACGGAGAUACAGAGCCUUGAGGUCUUUCAGUGGAAAGGUGGUUCAUGUUCAUUCUCAUCAGUGUGAAACUGAGGAGUCUGCAAUUUGGAAUAUGGAGAGAGAGACUGAUUUGCUGAAUUUCCUUCUAAAUGUCACUCAAAAAUUUCUUUUCCAUGUCAUUCUUGGGAAUGUCUUCCACAGGAUUUGAGAAUAGUUUCAUCUCAGCCCCCAUUAGAGAGAAGUUGGGGUGAAUUCUGGAAAAAUGUCUCUUUUUCCUGUGCCAUUUGCCUUCUGCUGCAACGAAAAUAUUUCCUGAUUCAAGAUUCUAUAAAAAGGAAACCAAGCAUAAGACUCUGUCAUCAUACCUGUUACACGUUCCUACAGGUGCACAAUCUAAGAGAGCUAAUUAACCUCAGAGUCUGGAGUUAACAGCUUUUCACCUUACUUCUCCUGUGAUCUAAUAUUAUCUUAGAAAAAUUAAUAUGCAAUUUCCAAAAGAUAUUUUGGUAAGACAACAACCUCCCAGUGAUAUGCCACCUUUCAAUUUUCCUUUUGUGGCAAUGAUUGCAUCUGAAGAAAGGAUCCCUGAGAGUCUCUGUUUCAUCAGGACAUUCUGAAAUUUACCCACAGUGAGGCUGUGGAUGGAUCAGGGGACCUGUAUAAAAUGUUUGAGCCUGUUCCAUUUUCCCGUGGAACCUGUUUCACUCAAUGCCAGGCAGUGCAGCAUUUAGGAAAGCAGUGCAGUACUCAGUAAGGCAGUGCAGUACUCAGUAACACAAUACAGUACUCAGGCAGUGCAGUACUCAGUAAGACAGUGCAGUGCUCAGUAAGGCAGUGCAAUACUCAGUAACAGUGUAGUACUCAGUAACAGUGAAGUACUCAGUAAUACAGUACAGUAUUCAGUAAGGCAGUGAAGUACUCAGUAAUACAAUACAGUACUCAGUUAGGCAGUGCAGUACUCAGGAAUGCAGCACAGUACUCAGGCAGUGCAAUACUCAGUGCGGUACUCAGUAACACAGUGCAGUACUCAGUAACAGUGCAGUACUCAGUAACAGUGCAGUACUCAGUAAGGCAGUGCAGUACUCAGUAACACAGUGCAGUACUCAGUAAUACAGUACAGUACUCAGUAAGGCAGUAUGGUACUCAGUAAAGCAAUGCAAUGCUCAGUAACACAGUGCAGUGCUCAAUAAGGCAGUGCAGUGCUCAGUAAGGCAGUGAAUUGCUUAGUAACACAGUGUAGUGCUCAGUAGGACAGCAUAGUACUCAGUAACACAGGGCAGCUAGUACUCAGUACUAUAAGUACUGAGUACUUAUAUAGGCAAUGUAGUACUCAGUAAAUCAGUGCAGUACUCAGUAAUGCAAGGGCAUUUCAGGCUCCUGCUGGGCUGCUUCUUUGGCCCAGCUGGGACUCCUAUUGAGACAGCUGCAAAACAGGCUGAUUUCAAUUAGGCAGCACUUCCCAAAGUGCACUGAGGAAGGUGGCCCCAAGAGAAGCUCUCUAAACAAAGGAGUACCCUCUCUGGUCAAGUACCUUUGGUAAAUACACCAUACCAUAAUAUCUGCUUGGAGAACCACAAUGCACAUUAGCAUAUUAGUCUGAGAGAGAACUUAUAGUAAGGAAACUCACUUGAUUUUAUCUAACCUCAAACUUUCCAAGUUUAAUGGAUCGUGAAUUUUUUUCAUGUAACUCCUAUUCAUAUCCCAUAGAUCUAGUAUUGUACAGCACUGCAUUCUCUGAGGAAGUCCCAGUCCAAACUCUGAUUUACAUCACUUUAGAAACCACACUCACACUUUUGCAGAGUGUUGAGCUUAAUAACUACCUGCCACAGAUUGGUAAAUUUAAUCCAGUGGUUGUUCUGUUUGUGCUUCUGUUCUCAUUUAUGUGUUUAGGGAUAGUGAGGUUCCUGCCUUCACUAGGAUCCACGGAUAUGAGACCAUUUUUGUCAUUUCCUGAAGUCACACUGGCGUUUCCAGAAGGCAUCUGGUGCUUUGCUCAGCCUUCCAUGCUGUGCAGCACUUCUGUCCUCAGUCAAGGAGAUGGCCAUGCUUAAGCCAGCAAUUGGCUGGGGUCCAGGAAACAAAGCAAAAGCACAAUAUGUGAAUGUGCUGAUUGUGUUCCCUAUGGCUUUAUCUCGAGCAAAAUACACUCUACAUAUUUUAAUAAUAAGUAUAAUUAGCUUGUUCCUGGACUUCAUUUUCAAUGAUGAACCAAAUUCCUGAAUUAUUUAUAAUUGUGUCUAAAGAAAAUUAUGAACUGGUCACAUGGCACUUGGAAUCCUUGAGUUAAUUCCAGUGAAGCAAAACUUGGGAAGAGUCAGGAUUGGCCACAUUGCCAAUAACAAAUUCCUACUUCGACAUAUGUCUUUUCAAAAAGCCUCCCAGACACAAGACAUCUUAACCGUCACUAGCCCAAGUGUUUUGUAUUACUCAGACACCAUCAUGAAAUAAUUCUGUGAGGUCAUGAUGUAUUUGAAAAUUCUGCAAGUUAAUAACUGCCUUGAAUUGUUUGAACCCGAAAUAAGGGUUCUUUGGUACCUCUAGUAGAUAGUGUGUUCAUUUCCCUGCUGCAAAUUUUGAAGUAUUUGGGCAGGUGAGUCAUGUUUUAACCACAAGCCAUAACUCAUCUGUUGUCUUUGCUUGGUCUUAGAGUAUCAUUCAGAAAGUCCGCUAAGGGCCAGCGUGCUUCUUCUGGCUACACAACCUUCUCAGGACAAGCCCACUGUCUUAAGCCACUUUGACCCUGGGAGACACAGGACUGUGUAUCCUCAAUCAUACUAUACAGCAGUUUUUGUCAGGGGAACAUAAAAAUAUCCAAGAGAGGUUAGGGCUUAGAUUUAAAAGCAUCAAAACAACAACAAUGGAAAUUUAUGUUGGCGAUAGCCAAGACCACAAGCAAAAGCACAUACUGGAAAUGAUGAGUUAGAAUCUGAUUUGACUGGGAUGUUUUAUGAGAAUGUAAGUGUGAUAUUAUACUGUCUGCCUUGCUGGAAUGCUGGCUUUCAAAUGGUCACCCAUUUUUCUUUCACUGGCCUGAGUUAGGACAUGCUAUCAGUAAUAGUCCCAGUUCCAUCCAACUUUCUGAAAUUUCAUUUUUUUUUUUGAGAUGGAGUCUCUCUCUGUCACCCAAGUUGGAGUGCAGUGGCCCCGCAAUCUCGGCUCACUGCAACCUCUACCUCCCAGGUUCAAGCUAUUCUACUGCCUCAGCCUCCCAAGUAGCUGGGGUUACAGGCAUUUGCCACCGGGCCCUGAUGAUUUUUGUAUUUUUAGUAGAGACAGGGCUUCACCAUGUUGGCUAGGAGGGUCUCAAACUCCUGACCUCAGGCGAUCCACCCCCACCUCGGCUUCCCAAAGUGCUGAGAUUACAGGUGUGAGCCACCGCACCCGGCCAACUUUCUGAAAUUUCAAAACUGAAUUGAUCCUUCUCCAAAUUAGUAUAUACUAUUGGAAACUUGUCUUUCCCUGCAGUAAGGCUGGUUUCCCCACCCCAGAAACAUGUAACGGUUGGUACCAUGCUAAGCCCUUGCCAUGCUAAGCCCUUUACAGUCAUAUCCUAUAAUCCCCAUAUCAACCUUAUAAGGAAGGUGUUUGUAGAUGAUGCAACUGAGCCUUAAGAGGACUAAUUCCCUUUUUCUAAGGCACAGAGCUGGUAAAAUGUGAAGUAAUAGUGAACCUAACAGUCAGAGACAGGCAGCAUGCUCUUAACUAGUGCUCUUCCUAAAGUUCCUUUAAUGUCCUUUUGAGAUUUUGAGCCAUGGAACUUACUUGUUCACCUGGCUAAGAACUCAUGGCCACUGUGGAAAUCUUGGUUAGGGAGUCAAAGAAACUGAGCCUGGGGCAAACGAGGCUUCCCACACUGCCAGGGGAGCCUCACUGUGAAGUCUAGGCUCAGACAGGCAUCAACAAACCUAUUCACCCCACCAUCAUCCUGAUCUAACCAUUCCCCAGUCAUCCCAGGAAAACCACUCACAGCCUGACACUGGGCUGACUUUCUUGAAGAUCCUCAUCCAAUUGGUGUUUUUCAGAAGUGUUCCAAUAUUAUGAAUUCUGUGUUGUGGAGAAAAGCAACCAUGCAUUUACUGGUCAAUGCCUUCUUGUAUAUGUAAUUCAAUACUUUUACUUUUAAUAUCCUCACCUUAUCUAAUCUUUGAAUUUUGUCAUGUAAUUUAUUGCUUCAUUAAGGUUACUUUUUGUUAUACAAAAUAAAAGCUGAUAUCCAAGGCAUGGUGCAUCUUGAUGAUUUUUUGUCCUUUGAAGUAUGGAUGAUAGAAAAAUGUAUCAGGUUUAUUCAUCUCAUCUUUCUGUUACAGGAUGAUUAAUUGUACAGUUACAUCACACGAAACAUUUAUAAUAAAGUCAUGCUUUAGAA